AUUUAGAUGGAGGUCGAUGAGCUGAACUGAGCCACCCAGAGACUUCAGGCAGAAAUCACCAACCUCAGGAAACAGAUGGGACCCCAACUCAGCAGUGUGCUGCCCUGCAAGACACCAUCCUGGAGGCAGAGCAGAAGGGCAAGGUAGCCAUCGGAGAUGCCCAGGACAAGCUGGCUGAGGUGGAGGCUGGACCAGCUGCUCUGUGAGUACCAGGAGCUGAUGAGCAUCAAGGUGGCCCUGGAGGGCCAGGCGUGCAGGAGUUGAUGCGAUUCCCAGCUGAGAUUGAAUUAUGAAUUAUGAAGCAGACUUGAGGUAUCCUUUCCUCUGACGUUGUUCUCCUCUGAGCCCCGUGAGAGGAUCUACUGAUUAUUCUGUUUUCAUGCGAACAGGCAAUCUAGAGAAGUCACCAACAACAUGAACUGCUCUACAUAGGUGGGGGUGGAUUUGCUGUGCGGUCAGGAUCCAACCUUCCCUUUUCCUGAGAGUAAAAGGAAGGAGCCUUUGGCCAGGCAGCUGGGGCCCUGGGGCCCUGAACUUGCUCUGUAGGCAUUGGCUGUGUGGCCUUGGGCAGGUCACUAUUUGUCCGUGGCCCUGUGGAGGUUCCUCCUCCACAGUAUAGGAGCUGCAGGGUUCCUCUUCCGUGUAGAAACUCACGCUGCAUCCACGUGGGGGAAGGGGAGACCCUGCCUUCAGGGCCCUUGCUGCCUGUGGUGGACACAUGGCCCAGACAGUGGGUGGUGUGGGAGCCCUGGCCACUGUUCCUUCAUGGGACACUUCAAGAAGGUGCCCCUCAAUGCUGUGUGAGAUGGAUAUUCAGGGAUGUAGAAGGGGUGUGGGGGUGCACAGAGCUGUCUCCCCACAGCUGUGGUGUCAAGCACUGUUUCAGCUCUCAGGCCACUGUGUCUGGCUUUUGCUCAGGGAACAGAGACUUCCUGAGAGGGGGCACCAUCCCCUGAGGAUCUGGUGCAGCAUCCAGGUUCGUGUCCAGGGCUGCCAGGUCCUUGGGGGCCAGCUGGAGGGUCCAGACCUCAAGCUAGGAAUCCUGCACAUGCUGGUCCUGACUUGGGAGAUGAGGAGUCAAGUUUAAUGAGAGUCCAGGUCUCCAACUCAGGGCACAGAAACCUGUGGGUCUCCCUCCCAGAGGCAAAGGCCAAUCUUCUGGCCCUGCUCUCUCCUGGUAUCUGUCUGCCUGAGCACGCAUACCUGCUCUGGCUCUACCCCCACCUUUUUGUCUUCUAUGGCAAUGUGGAGAUGGGCUUUUGGGUCAAAACAAAUUCUUUUUCUUUUCUCCCUCAUGCAUCCAAAUGCCAGGCCCCAGAAGAAAGCCCCUCUCAGUGGGCCUUUGGUGUCAGUCACCUUCUCCCUUGUCUCUCCCUGCAGGCUCGUAGUGCUCUUAGCCCACACUGUCUCCUUCUGUGAUGCAGAAGCAAGAGCUCUUCUCCUAUCUCUGGUACUGAAGUAAGGGCAUGCAUAAACACCUUUUGAAACAUGAUUACUAUCAAUUCUCAGUUAUCCACCUUAGUGGAUGUCAGCCAUGGUACUGAUUAUCUGCAACCAUGUUUAGCAAGAAGUUGUUUUUGUUUCAUUUUACAAGGCCUCCUAUGACCUAUUCUAAGGCAGAGGGACUCUCUGCCUUCCACGGAUUCGUAGACCCUGGGUGGCCACAAAAGGGAGGAGGAGAGAGGAAGAUCUAUGGGGACUGGGAGGGUGAAAGUGUGCCAGCCCGGCCCCACCCCAUUCCCUGAGAAAGCCAGGUGGAUUAUCCACCUGGAGAGCAACCUGAGGGUGGGCUGGGUUCAGGUGUCUCCCCUUCUGCCGGAAUGAGUAUAAAAACAUAGCAGAAGCAAAUCCAUCAUAAGGGCCAUACUUCAGGCAGAGUCUAGUUUGAAAUGAUGUCCAGUGUGACCUGCUGGGCUAUGAGGGGUGUGACUAGAGCCCUGGAGCCCUCCAGUUUAUGAAGGAGAUCUUGCAUCCUGUGUUUUGUUUAAAGGGUUGCCCACUCCCACCUUACCCUCUCUCCCACACCUCUCCAAUAAACUUCAUGGGGAAUUUAUUCUGUUUGGAAACUUUAAAAAUAUUCACUAAUAAGAUCUUCCCUGAGUAUUGUUCACUACCCCCAGAUUGCCAUCCUGCAAGGCACACAUGUGCACAUGUGCACACACACACACACACAUGUUCAUUCUGUUCUAUCCUUGCUUGGCUGUCUGUGCUGACAGGAGGGAACACUGGAAGGGGUGCUAUUCCUGUUUGGCUUUGGAAGGUUGGCACAAAGGACCCUUGUUUCCUCUCUCUAUUAGGAAAACUCAGCUUCCGUUUUUACAGCAAUAACUUCAGGCCUUGAGCCUUGUUUGGUGGCCAAGCUGGUGUUAUUAUUGGCUAAUUGCAGGGUAAUAGUGUUGCUAUCAUUAUUGCUAGGAGGACUAUUAUCAGGUAACUAAAUGGCCAGAGGGUGUGGAGUGGGAAAAGCAGCCUGGGGGCUUGGGUCACAAGGGCAACUCUCCUGUUUCGUCUCCUGCUUUGCUCAGAAGGCAGUUUCCAGUCCAGCACUGCACUUGGAGUCCAGAGGUGUUGUAUUGGAAGGCAGGUCUUGUCAAAAGUUCCCUGCUGUGAGCUCUGUUUUGAGCAGCAAGGGGAGGAAGAUAGCCAGGGAUAAUGGUGCACAGGUCCUGCCUUUGAGCCACUCCUACACUUCUGAAGAGGCAGCAUGCAUUCAUUCAACAACCAUUUAUGUGCCAGAUUGUUCUCAACACUAAUACAAAAGGGUGAUCAAGACUUCUGGCUACUGGGAAGCAGGUAAGUGAAGGUGCACAGUAUAGUGAGACAGAUGCUAUCUUGGGAAGAGCAUCUCAGGAACAAGAGACCCAGAUUAGGAGGAUAAGGGAGACUUCCUUGAUGAAGAUUUCUCAAAGCUGAAACCUGAAACCUGAAAGAUGAAGAGUUAGCCAAGGGGAAGGGAGUGUUUAAGUAGAGGUGCUGUAUCUACUGUGAACAGAGCAGUGCUGGGCACAUAAGUAGGUGCACCAUAAAUGGUUGAAAUGGUCAAAUGAAAGAAAAGGAGAUUGACAAGAGCAUAAGAAACUGCAGUCUGGUGGAGCUUGCAGAGAGAUGUGGCAGGACAGGUGGGUGGGGCAAGAUCAGGACAAGAGAGCCCUUCCGGGUAGAGUGGCCACCUUGUUCCUGUUUGCCUGGAACUUUCCUAGUUUUAAAACUGAAAGUCCUACAUCCUGAGAACCCAAUAAGCCCAGGCAAAUGGAAAAUGUUGGUCAUCCUAUGGCUGCGUUGCCUUCCCAGAUUUGGACUCCAUGCUGCAGCUUUGAGCAGUGGACUAUUAGACACAAUGGCAAGAAUGCUUGCUUACCUAGCAGGCAGAGCAUAGCUGAGCCUGCUGGGUGCCUCCCCACCCCGCCCCUUAUCCUUUCUCCUUUCACAGAAGUAGAAAUUUAGAUGAGCACAUGGCCAGCCACCCAAAGAUGACAUUUCCCAGCCUCCCUUGAAAAUAACUAUGGCCAUGAAACUAAGCUCUGGUCAGAGGGAUACGAGUUGUGGUAUCUUGCUCCUGAUUGUGCUGUUAAAAGGCACAACUCCUGAGAGUGGGUUCAGGCUCUGAUGAAAACAAUAUGAGGAAGUUUAAGAAACUCUCCAAGCUCAAGACCUGACCCAGACCUUUUCAAUAAGAAUCUCAGGGUCAGGGAAAGUAGGGAUUUUAGAAAGAUCUCAGGCAGUAGUGGUUAAAAGGAUGGACUCUGCAGUGGGCUGCCUGGCUUCCAGUCCUGGUUCUAGCUAUGUGACCUUGUGCAAGUAACUUAACCUUCUGUGCUUCAGUUUUCUUAUCCAUAAACUGUGUGUUAACUGAACCUUCUUGAUGGGGUUAUUUUGAAGAUUAGUGUGCUCAGAACAGUACCUGUCAUAUACAUGCUUAAUUUAUUAAUGUGCUCAGUAAACAUUGCAAGAUGUACUAUCGCAUAUCACAACCAGGAUAUUGACAUUUAUACAAUUAAGAUACAGAACUUUACCAUCAUCACAAAUUUCCCUCAUGUUGUCCUCAUUUGGACACACCCACUUCUCUCCUGUGACACUGUUUAACCCCCAAGCAAUUACUAAUCUGUUCCCCAUUUCUGUAUUUCAAGAAUGUUAUAUAAAUGGAAUCUUUUUGAGAGUAUUACAUAAAUGGAAUCAUACAAUAUACAAAUCAUACAAUCCCUGAGGAUUUUUUUUUUUACUCAGUAUAAUUCUUUAGAGAUUCACAUGGGUCAUUGCAUGUAGUGAUAGUUUAUUUCUUUUCAUUGCUGAGUAGUACUCUAUGACAUGAAUGUACCACGGUUUGCCACCCAUUGAAGGGCACCUGGAUUGUUUGCAUUUUUUGGCUAUUACAAAUAAAGCUGCUAUAAAUGUUUGCAUACAGGUUUUUGUGUGAACAUAGAUUUCAUUUCUCUGGGAUAAAUGAUCAGGUUUGUAAUUGCUGGGAUGUAUGAGAGUUGCUUGUUUGGUUCUUUAAAAACUGCUAAACUGUUUUCCAGAGUGGCUGUGCCAUUUUACAUUCUCAUUAGCAAUAUAUGAGUGCUCUAGUUUCUCUGGGUCCUUGCCAGCAUGUAGUGUUGCCACUAAGUCUUAUUUAAGCCAUUCUGAUAGGUGUUGAGUAAUAUCUCAUUGUGGCUUAAAUUUGUAUUUCUCUAAUGUUGAAUUUCAUUUUGUGUGCUUAUUUGCCAUCGGUAUGAACUAUUCAGUGAAAGUCUUGUGAUGUUUUUGCCCAUUUUCUAAUGCAAUUGCUUGUUCUUUUGUUGUUGAGUUCUGAGAGUUCAUUAUGUAUUCUAGAUCCUAGUCCUAUGCUGAAUAUGUGGUCUGCAAAUAAUUUUUCCUAGUCCAUUGCUUGUCUUCUCAUCCUCCUUAACAAGGUCUUUUGCAGUACAAAGUUUUUAAUUUUGAUGAAGUCCAGUAGAUUUUUCCUUAUAUGGAUUAUGCUUUUGAUGUCAAAUCUAACACCUCUUUACCUACCCUUUAUCUUGAGGAUUUCCCCUAUUGUUUUUCUAAAAGUUCUAUAGUUUUACAUUUUAUAGUCAAUUAAGUCUGUGAUCUAUUUUGAGUUAAUUUUUGUGCAAAAUAUGAAACUUAAAUCAAGAUUUUUUGUUUUAUUUUUGUUUUGCCUAUUUGUAUAUAAUUACUUCAGCAUCAUUUGUUGAAAAGGCUAACUUUCUUCCACUGAAUUAUUUUUGACUCUGUCAGAAACUAGUUGAGGUCCAAUUUAUCUAUUUUUUUUUUUUGUUUUGUUGUCGCUUGUGCUUUUUGUUUCUGUUAUGGGUUGAAUUGCAUUCUCCAAAAAAGAUAUGUUAAAGUCCUAACUCCCAUUACCUCCAAAUGUGAAUGUAUUUGCAAAUAAUGUGCUUUAAAAAUUUUCUUUUGAGACUUCCUCUUCAACCCAUGAGUUAUUUAGAUGUAUAUUGUUUAGUUAAUAAGUGUUUGGAUAGAUCCUGUUAUCUUUCCUUUGUUUACAUUCAGUUUAUUUAUUUUGGCUAGAGAACAUACUCUGUAUGGUUUAAGUUAUUUACAACUUGUUGAGGUUUAUUUUAUAUCCCAGAGUAUGGCCUAUCUUGGUAUAUGUCCUGUGGGCACUUGAAUAGAAUAUUUAUUCUGCUUUUGUUAGGUAGAAUGUUUAUAAAUAUCAAUUAGAUCCUGUUGGUUGAUGGUACUGUUAAGUUCUUUUAUAUCCUUGAUAAUAUUCUUGCUAAUUGUUCUAUUGACUGUGAGAAAGGAAUAUUGGAGUCCUUAACUAUAAUUGUGGAUUUGUCUAUCUAAUAUUUUAGUUCCAUCAGUCUUUCAUUCACAUAUUUUGCAACUCUUUUGUUUGGUGUAUAAACAUUAGGAAUGUCUUCUUACUAAAUCACUAUUUCUUCUUGGUGAAUUGGUCUUUUUAAAUUAUACACUGUCUCUCUCUGUCUCAUAAUUUUUUUGCUUUGAAGUAUACUUUAUCUGAUGUUAAUCUAGACACUUAUAGUUGAGAUAAGUUUUUGGAGAUAGCAUAUAGUUGGUUCAUGUUUUAAAAUAUACUCCGCCAAUCUCUGUCUUUUAAUUGGUACAUUUAGGCCAUUUAUAUUUAACAUAAUUAUUGAUAUAUUAGGGCUUAAGCUGCCAUUUAAAUUUUUGUUUUCUAAUUGUUCUCUUUUUUCUAUUUAUGUUUUUCUCCUACUGUCCUGUUGGUUACUUGAACAUUUUUAAGAAUCCAUUUUGAUUUAUGUAUUGUGUCUUUUAGUAAACGUUUUUGUAUAGCAUUUUUAGUGCUGCUGAGUAUUUUAUUAUAUAUACAUAACUUAUCACAGUCUAUUGCUAUCAUUAUUUUAUCAGUUGAAGAAUCCUUACCUCUUUAUAUUCCUUUACCGUCUCUCAUUUAUAAUAUAAUUUCUUAAAUAUUUCAUCUAAAUACAUUUAGAAUCACAUCAGACAGUGUUAGAAUUUUUGCCUCAACCAUUGAACAUAAUUUAUAGGAAAUUCAAGAGAAGGAAAGUCUAUUGUAUUAACUUAUUUUUUAAAAAUUAUCAUGUUUUUUCCUCCUUCCUAAUGUUUCAAGUUGUCUUCUUUUAUCAUUUUCUUUCUGUUUAGAGAACUUACUUUAGCCAUUCUUUUAGGGUAGGCCUGCUGGAAACACAUUCUUAGUUUUUCUUCAUCUGAGAAUGUUUUCAUUUUGUCUUCAUUCCUGAAGGAUAUUUUUACUGGGCACUGAAUUCUGCAUCAACAGUUCUUUGCUUUCAGCACUUGAAAACUAUGCCACUCCCUGCUAGCCUCCAUAGUUUAUGAUGAGAAAUCUUCUGUCCUUCAAAUUGUUUUUUCCCUAAAGGUAAAGCAUUGUUUCUCUUUAGCUGCUUUCAGGUUUUUAUUUGUAGUUUUCAGAAUUCUGACUAUAAUAUGUCUAGGUAUGAAUUUCUUUGGGUUUAUUCUGUUUAGGGUUUGCUCAGCUUCCUGAAUCUGUGGGUUUACGUCUUUUGCCAAAUUUGGGGAAUUUUUAUUCCUUAUUUCUUUGAGUUAUUUUUCAGCAAUACUUCUUUUCCUUUCCUUCUGAACCCCAGUGACUUGACUGUUAGAUCUUUUGUUAGAGUCUCCCUGAUCCUGAGACUUGGUUCAUUUUAUUCUUCUUCAGUCUGUUGUUCAGUUCUCUUUAUUAUUCAGAUUGGGUAAUUUUUAUUGUCCUCUCUUCCAGUUCACUGAUUCUUUCCUCUGGCCUUUUAUUCUCCUGUUACGUGUAUCCAUUGAGUUUUUUAUUUUGAUUAUUAUAUUUCUUAGUUCUAAAACUUCCAUUUAAAGAUCCAGAAGCUGAUGGAUGUGGGUCUGAUCGCAAUUCAGUGAUGACUUGUUCAUCCUCCACUUCCCUUCGCCCUCGUGUGGAAAGAGGAGCUGGGACUGUGGCAGGCAGCAAGGAGCGGAAGGGAGAGAAAUGGGAUAGAAGGCCUCAUUUCUAUAUAUUUAUACACAACCCCAGGGAAGGCACAGAGACUUGUACUUGCACUGUUCAUGCUGUCACUGCCUCUGGGCCCUCCCAGCACACGUGUGGUCUCUUCACCACUGCCCUCCAGUUCCGUGUCUCCUUCUUCUGCCCCCAGUUGCUGUCUCAGCUGCUCUCCCAGAGUUGGUUAUUUUUAGUUUGGGGCAGUAGGCAUAUAUGGGGAGGAGAGGGGGUUCUUCCCAGACUCACAUCCCAGAUGUUUAUUCCAUGUCCUCUUCUCCAAUAAAACAAGCAAGUUGGGGAUGUUUAUAAAAAAAUAAAAAAUAAAUAAAACUUUCAUUUAGUUCUUCUGGUUUUUAAAUUUCUUUGUUGAAACUGUCUAAUUUGUCAUCUAUUUAGCAUGUUCUUAGUUGUUCAUUUAAGCAUGUUUAUUGUGGCUGCUUUGAAAUCUUUGUCAGAUAAUUUUAACAACUUUGUCAUCUAAGUAUUGGCAUCUAUCAAUCGUCUUUUUUUUUCAUUCAAUUUGAGGACUUCCUUGUUCUUGGCACAAUGAGUGAUUUUUUAAAUAAACAUUUGGACAUUUUGGUACUAUUAUGAGAUUCUGGAUAUUGUUUAAAUCUUCUGUUUUGGCUGCCUUCUUCUGACAUUGUCCUUGCAGGGGAAAGGGUGUGGAUGCUACCUUGUUAUUGCCAGGUGAGGGUGGAAGUCUGGGCUCCCCACAUGGUCUCCACUGGUACCAAGUGGGUCAGGCACUUGUUACCUCCUGGUGGGGAUGGAAUCCCGGCUUCUUUCUUGGACUUCCCUGAUUCCAUCUAACUGCUGGGGGAGGGGGCAGUUGGGGCACCUCAUUAUAGCCUGGUGAGUGUGAAGGUCUAGGCCUCACACUCAGCUUUUGCUGAUGUGGGUGUAGGUGAAACCAUAGUAUUUUCUGUGUGUUGAGAUGGAAUAGAGUGAUUAUUCUCUGUAAGUUUUCCAUCUUGCUAGGCUGCCCCUUUCCUGAUGAUGUGGCUACAGAGAUCAAGCUUUUGUUUAAUCUUUAAAAAUCUGAGCCUUUCCAGAUUCCUGCCUUCUUCUGCCCCAAGUCUGGAAUAUAGGAGACAAAUAGAAAACCUAGAGAAAUAAUCAUCAUGUCUUUCACUGGGUCCUGAGGUCCCUGUUGGUGUGCCUUCUUCUCUACGCUUCAGAGUCUUCUUAUGUUUGUGAAGAAGGGAAAAGUAUGUCUACUUCAUCUUUCUAGUUGUGGAAUAUCCACAUAGGGAAUACUGAUUUCACAAUAUUUAUUUGAUUGCCCCUGGGGGUGACAGAAAGUUGAUUUCCUGCCUGUCUCUCUCUCUCUUUCUCUCUCCCCCCCCCCCCCUUUCUUUCUCUCUUUUCUGAAACCAUCAGAAACUCUUGCCCUAGUGUCUGGGCAGAGGCUAAUGGCAGGACAGCCCCACUGUGGGAAGUGGGGCUGACUUGGUAAUUGGGUUCAUCUGGCAUUGAGUUUCCCCUGGUGAGGGCAAUAUAAGGGAUGUGAAAUAUAAGGAGCUCACUGUGUGAAAACCCACUUAGAGGCAUUUCAAUGACAGGUGCUAGGGAUACUGUUCUUAGGGAGAAUGAUUUCAAAGGGCACCUAAGAGUUUUUUAGCCUAGUCCAUGACUGCCUGAGAGUCCUUUGCCACUGGAGUUCUGGGAAGUGAGUAGAGAGGACCAAAGGGAGGAUAGGACCUGGAUCUUGUCCUCAGGAAAAUUUCUGGCCGUUAGGAAAGAUUGACAUACCUCCUGAACACAGGUAGAGACAUCAAAUUAGAAGAGACAAUUGACAUAAUAGAUGCUGUUGUUUGGACAACAAACAACAUGUGGGAGGCUGGGAAGAGAGGUGUGAUUGGAUUAGGAAAGUGAUCAGAGAAGGUUUCCGGAAGUGCCUCUGUGGCAGGUUCACAAGAUGAGAAGGCCAGGGAGGGGAGGGGAAGUGAAAACCAUAAGGAGAGGGGCUGUUUGCUCGUAAGCACAUCCACGCCAUACUGCAGAGUUGGCAUUCACAGCAUAAAUGCCAUUGGGGGUUAUCUCAGGGCCUGUGACAUGCAGCAAUUUGUAGUUUUGCUGAGAUGCAGGCCUGAAUCACCUCCACCCCAGUGCUGGUGUGCUGAAAUGAGCCAAUUAGGGAGUGAUUCUGGCUGGAAUACUAAGCAUUCUCAUCACAAUGCAGUUUUGUUGGUCUUCUUUGUGCCUUACAAAGAAACUUACAAAGGAAUAGAAACUUUGGGUCAGGUGCGGUGGCUCACGCCUGUAAUCCCAGCACUUCGAGAGACUGAGGCGGGCAGAUCACCUGAGGUUGGGAGACCGAGACCAGCCUGACCAAUAUGGAGAAACCCCAUUUCUACUAGAAAUACAAAAUUAGCCGGGCGUGGUGUUGCAUCCCAGCUACUCAGGAGGCUGAGGCAGGAGAAUCCCUUGAACCCAGGAAGUGGAGGUUGCGAUGAGCCGAGAUCAUGCUAUUGCACUCCAGCCUGGGCAAGAAGAGUGAAACGCCAUCUCAAAAAAAAAAAAAAAAAAAAAGAAAAAAAGGAAUAGAACUUCAUGUUAGCUAAAAAAGAUUAAAGGACUUCCAAGUGGCAUUGCCUUUAGUGAAAUUGAAGACAUCAAAGAAAAUGAUUAUUCUUAACUAGAAAACAACCAUAUUGUAUAAAACAGAGGGGAGGUUGAAUUUGGCAAUUGCUUAGUACAACAAUUUUAGAGGCAUAUCAUAACCUCUAUACAGAAAUAGAAAAGAAGGAUGGGCCAACUGUUCAUUCAAGUACUCCAGCUAGUGAAAUACUUGUGUUUUUAUGGAGGAAAUUCUAUACUAUGGAUAUAUUUGGGAUUUGGGAUUUGGGAAACUCUUGGGUCACAUACUUUGGCAAUGUCAAGGAUCCAUGAAAUUCAAAUGUCUUCCCCUACCUCCCCAUCUCCAAAAUUGUGAGCUAGGUUUGGUCUUCAUAAUUCGGGACCCAAGAGCCUAGCACAGUACCUGGGAGAGAGUCAGCCCUCAAGAGAAGUCUGUUAAACGAAUGGAUAAAUGAAUGAACAAGUAGAUGGCUGGCUGGCUGGUUGGACGGAUAGAUGGACGAAUGAAUAAGGCGGGCAUAGCUCUGAAUGUGGAGUCAGAAGACCAGCCAAGGGAGUCCUCAAGGCUGGGGCCUGUGCUUUUUGGGGGCAUUUUCAUUCUCUGGGAUUCACACAAAGAAAGGACUCACUAAAUGUUUGCUAAAGGAAUGACAUCCUCAAUUAUCUGAACCUUGGUUUCCCCAUUUGUGUAAUGUGGAUCAUCACCAUUCCCCUCCAUGCAGACUAAGUGGAUUAAAUGAGCUUCUUGUGUGAGGAGCUCUGUUACACUGUAAAGUGCUGCACCAGUGUCAGCCAUCGUGAAUGGUGCAAUGACCAUAAUUUCAAGGUCAAGAGUCAGGGUAGUGGGAUGGUAAAGGGAAAAAGAAGUCAGUGUGUGCAAAGGAAGGUGAGCAGGGCAGCCCGGCUGGCACAGAGGAGCAGGAGAGCUGCCUGGGAGGGCACAGCAGGGGGCUGGCAGCCAGAGGCUGGUCCUGGAUUCCCAGUGUGCUCCUCUCCUAUGGCCCUGGCCAGCCAUCAAACCUGUCUCCAGGAACUCUGGGAAGCCAGGCAGCAGCAGCCUCUUCUUAACCACAUAAAAGCAGCUCAGCCAGGGUCCCUGAAGCAGCCCAUCUGAUGCUGGCAUGGUUGUGAGAUUUCUAACAGAUGACACUGUCAAUUAAAGGUCUCCCCUCUGUACCCCUACAAUCCCAGGCCCCACCACUCCCUGGGGAACAGCAAUUGAGACUGCGACAAACCUCCCACCUAAGAUCUUUCUAUGGAUAAUGUGCCCAUGCUAAUUACACAUGUUCAUUAGAUAAAACUCAAAUUACAUGAGCAAGACUUGCAAGACUAGCACUUUGGGAGUUUUCAAGUCAUUUACCUGGUGUCUGAUUUUGCUGGGAGAAAAUGAUUUCUUGCUUCCAGGCAAACUGAACCCACAAAUUAGGCCCAUGGCUCCCUCUUGAGUCCUAUAAAGUGGGAGCCCAGGAUCACAGGCUGGUGAACUGCAUCUCAGCUAAGGGUCAGCAUCUUAUCCCCACUUUCUGGCCUCCCCACCAUGAGCCGCCAAUUCACCUACAAGUCGGGAGCUGCUGCCAAGGGGGGCUUCAGCGGCUGCUCCGCUGUGCUCUCAGGGGGCAGCUCAUCCUCCUACCGAGCAGGGGGCAAAGGGCUCAGUGGAGGCUUCAGCAGUCGGAGCCUUUACAGCCUGGGGGGUGCCCGGAGCAUCUCUUUCAAUGUGGCCAGUGGCAGUGGGUGGGCAGGAGGCUAUGGAUUUGGCCGGGGCCGGGCCAGUGGCUUUGCUGGCAGCAUGUUUGGCAGUGUGGCCUUGGGGUCCGUGUGUCCGUCGUUGUGCCCGCCCGGGGGUAUCCAUCAGGUCACCAUCAACAAGAGCCUCCUGGCACCCCUGAACGUGGAGCUGGACCCUGAAAUCCAGAAAGUGCGUGCCCAGGAGCGGGAGCAGAUCAAGGUGCUGAACAACAAGUUCGCCUCCUUCAUUGACAAGGUGCGGUUCCUGGAGCAGCAGAACCAGGUGCUGGAGACCAAGUGGGAGCUGCUACAGCAGCUGGACCUGAACAACUGCAAGAAUAACCUGGAGCCCAUCCUUGAGGGCUACAUCAGCAACCUGCGGAAGCAGCUGGAGACGCUGUCUGGGGACAGGGUGAGGCUGGACUCGGAGCUGAGGAGCGUGCGCGAAGUGGUGGAGGACUACAAGAAGAGGUAUGAAGAAGAAAUAAACAAGCGCACAACUGCUGAGAAUGAAUUUGUGGUGCUUAAGAAGGACGUGGACGCAGCUUACACGAGCAAAGUGGAGCUGCAGGCCAAGGUGGAUGCCCUGGAUGGAGAAAUCAAGUUCUUCAAGUGUCUGUACGAGGGGGAGACUGCUCAGAUCCAGUCCCACAUCAGCGACACGUCCAUCAUCCUGUCCAUGGACAACAACCGGAACCUGGACCUGGACAGCAUCAUUGCUGAGGUCCGUGCCCAGUAUGAGGAGAUCGCCCGGAAGAGCAAGGCCGAGGCCGAGGCCCUGUACCAGACCAAGUUCCAGGAGCUGCAGCUAGCAGCCGGCCGGCAUGGGGAUGACCUGAAACACACCAAAAAUGAGAUCUCAGAGCUGACCCGUCUCAUCCAAAGACUGCGCUCGGAGAUUGAGAGUGUGAAGAAGCAGUGUGCCAACCUGGAGACGGCCAUCGCUGACGCCGAGCAGCGGGGGGACUGUGCCCUCAAGGAUGCCAGGGCCAAGCUGGAUGAGCUGGAGGGCGCCCUGCAGCAGGCCAAGGAGGAGCUGGCACGGAUGCUGCGCGAGUACCAAGAGCUUUUGAGCGUGAAGCUGUCCCUGGAUAUUGAGAUCGCCACCUACCGCAAGCUGCUGGAGGGCGAGGAGUGCAGGAUGUCCGGAGAAUAUACCAACUCCGUGAGCAUUUCGGUCAUCAACAGCUCCAUGGCCGGGAUGGCAGGCACAGGGGCUGGCUUUGGAUUCAGCAAUGCUGGCACCUACGGCUACUGGCCCAGCUCUGUCAGCGGGGGCUACAGCAUGCUGCCUGGGGGCUGUGUCACUGGCAGUGGGAACUGUAGCCCCCGUGGGGAAGCCAGGACCAGGCUGGGGAGUGCAAGUGAAUUCAGGGACUCCCAGGGAAAGACCUUAGCUCUAAGCUCACCCACCAAAAAAACCAUGAGAUAAAAGUGCAACACAGCCCAUUUCCCAGUAGUCUGCCUUGCCCUGGCAGACUGCUCCGGACUCUUCUAGGAAAUUCCUCUGUCUCAUUUGUCCUCAUCUCCUUCUUGCUUUGCUUUGCUGUGGACCUCUCCUCCUUCUCCUUGACCUCUCUGCCUCAGUCUUUGUUAAUGUUGAAUCAGGAUUUGAGAGCUGGAGCCCAUCUUUCUGCCUCCAUCCAAAGAGGCCUUUUAACUCAGCCUCCCCUUCUGGAAGAAGACUUGGCCUUUUCUCUGCCUGCAUGUCCCUGUGCAGAGGAAGGCUGUCUCUCAAGGGUAACCCCAAUCUGCCUGUGCUGCUCUUUCAUACCCUGUCUCAGUAACUAUUUGGCCAUGUGCUCCCUGGGUACACAAGUUUUCAGAUCUACUGAUAGACCUGCAGGAACUCUCUCAUGUUAGAGCAAUACUGGCUCAGGCAAAACACCUGGUGGGAAGUUGUAUCUUGUAUAGCCACUGCAUAUUACAUAGCCAGGAGUACCCCUUGAGGCUAAUUCUACCAACCAAGGGAUUUGUGCUCUUCAUCUGUGGGUACUUGUCCUUGUUUAGGCCUCACCUCCCUGCUCCUGUGUCUUACCAAUAAACUUAUAAAGCCCA